GUUGCCCAGCGAACCGCCACAACAGAGAGCGGACUCGAUCCUGCGCUCCGGCCGGGCUGACCUGCCUGCGUCCAGCCCCCGCGCCCUGGGCCUGCCUGGGUCUGGAUCUGUGUCCGAGUCUGGGUCUGGAUCUGGGUCCGAGUCUGGGUCUGGCCCUGCGCUCAGGGCCCGCGGAGGAGACUAUGGACCCCGCCGGGCGCGCCCGGGGCCAAGGGGCCACGGCAGGGGGGCUGCUGCUCCGGGCUGCUGCGGCCGCCAAGGGUCUCAGGGAAGACCUGUGGGGCGCGGCCGCCCUGCCUUGGAGGAGCCUGUCCCGGAUCCCGAAGCGGGAGGGUCUUGGAGAGGAGGACACAGCAGUUGCCGGACACGAGCUCCUACUCCCAAAUGAGAGAAGCUUUCAGAAUGCUGCUAAAAGCAAUAAUUUGGAUCUUAUGGAGAAGCUGUUUGAAAAGAAGGUUAACAUUAAUGUUGUGAACAAUAUGAACCGCACAGCCCUGCAUUUUGCAGUGGGGAGAAAUCAUUUAUCUGCAGUGGAUUUCUUGCUUAAACACAAGGCCAGGGUGGAUGUUGCUGAUAAGCACGGCUUGACAGUAAUUCACCUUGCAGCCUGGUCUGGGAGCCUUGAGGUCAUGCUCAUGCUGGUUAAAGCUGGAGCAGACCAGAGAGCCAAGAAUCAGGUAGGUAUGUGGGUCACACCUGGACAAAAGCUCUUACCUCACCAUUGCAGGAGAGAGGAAGUUCUGAGGUCACUGUCUAUCUCCCCCACCCCUGGUUCUCUUCAGGAUGGAAUGAGCGCCCUCCACUUUGCCACUCAGAGCAAUCAUGUGCGCAUCGUGGAGUAUCUUAUUCAAGAUCUGCACCUCAAGGACCUGAACCAGCCUGAUGAGAAAGGAAGAAAACCAUUUCUUUUGGCAGCUGAGAGGGGCCAUGUUGAAAUGAUAGAAAAACUUACCUUCCUAAACCUGCAUACUUCAGAAAAGGACAAGGGGGGAAACACUGCCUUGCACCUCGCUGCGAAGCAUGGUCACAGUCCUGCAGUGCAGGUGCUGCUAGCCCAGUGGCAAGACAUAAAUGAGAUGAAUGAGCUCAAUAUCAGUAGUUUGCAGAUAGCAACCAGGAACGGCCAUGCAUCCCUUGUCAACUUUCUUCUCAGUGAGAACGUUGAUCUGCACCAGAAAGUGGAACCUAAGGAGUCCCCUCUUCAUUUAGUUGUUAUCAACAACCACAUCACGGUUGUAAACAGUUUAUUAAGUGCACAGCAUGAUAUUGACAUCUUAAAUCAGAAGCAGCAAACCCCUCUGCAUGUAGCUGCUGAUCGUGGAAAUGUGGAACUGGUGGAAACCCUGCUGAAGGCAGGCUGUGACUUGAAGGCUGUUGACAAGCAAGGAAAGACUGCCCUGGCUGUGGCCUCCAGGAGCAACCAUAGCCUUGUCGUGGGCAUGCUCAUUAAAGCAGAGAGAUACUACGCCUGGAGAGAGGAGCAUCAUGAGAGCAUCAGGGACCCGUCAACAGGCUUUACUCUGACAUUCAAGCAAGAUCACAGUCUGGAGACCAGACACAUUCGCACGCUUCUCUGGGACCUGGCUUACCAUCAGCUGAAGGCCAAUGAGUGGCAGAGGCUGGCCCGUUCGUGGAACUUUACAGAUGACCAGAUUAGAGCCAUUGAGGAGCAGUGGUCGGGAAAUGAAAGCUUCCGUGAACAUGGCCACAGGGCUCUGCUUAUCUGGCUACACGGGACCCUGAUGACUCAGGGUGACCCGGCCAAGCAACUGUAUGAAGAGCUGGUACACGCAGGUUUCCCAAAACUAGCUGAAAAGACUCGUCAUUUCAAAAGCAAAACUGACUCAAACUCCAAGAAAUGUGUAGUUUCAUAAAUGCCUAAAGAAAUUGUAUUUACAUGAUUUUCCACUCAGCAUUCAGUUCUUUUAAUGCCAUAAAUUUCUUCUAGCAGUAGCACUGAUUUUCAACUAUGAUGAUGGUGGUGACAGGGAACUCUAACAGAUGAAAGAAGAGUAAUACCAUGAUACUUUUCAACCACUAAAAAGUCAAAUAUAGUUUUUUUUGCUGAGGGCAAGUUGUAUGUGAUUUUCCCAUUUCUAUCAAUCAUUUGAUGUAAUCCAUGUAAUAAGAUAAUCUAGGACGGUUUUGUAUGUCAUGUUUUUUUAAAAAACUCAUGGGAGCAGCAUCAUGGUACAGUAAAAAAACAAGGGUUUUUAUAAUAGACAAAUAUGGUUUUGAACUUGGUUUUGCCACUUAUUAGAUGUGAACCUUUGGGCAUGUUAAUGUUGUUUACGUUCUUAGAUCUUCAGUUUCCUUCUCUAUAAACUGGGAGAGAUGUCUAUUUAAUCCAUAGGGUUGGAAUGAAGAUGAAGGGAAAAUGCCUGUGUAGCCUCACGCCCAUAGUACGGAAAUCAACUGCUAUUUCUCUUUCAGUAAGAGAAACUGGGUUUGGAAUUUAUAGUCAUUGUUGACUUUAAAUCACACAUUUUGUGUAAUAUAUUACUUAGGAAAGACCAGAAGUAUGUACACCAUUUUUUUUUUUUUUUAAAUCUCUUGGUGAUGUAAUUACAGAUGAUUAUUUUCUUUGUACUUUUGGGUACAUUCCAUUCUUUUUUUCACAAAGAACAUGCAUUAUUUUUGUAAUCUAAGAGUUAUGAAAUAAAUGUAAAAUUGAGUGUCA